AGAAUGUGCUCUGGAGAUUUAAAUUUUCCCAGCUUAAGGGAUCUUCAGAUGAUGGGAAAACUCGAGUAAAGCUGCUGUUUCAGAAUCUGGACACCAAACAGAUUGAGAUGAAGGAACUCGAGUUCCAGGACCUGAGGGCUGUCCUGCACUGCAUCCACUCCUUCAUAGCAGCCAAGGUGGCCUCCGUGGACCCCGGCUUCAUGGACAGUCAGAGUCUUGCCAGAAAAUACAUGUACAGCAGCUAAAGGUUGUUUCUGUUGAGUGCUGAAAAAUUAAAUUAUUUUCGUAAGAAAUGAUUCUUUCCUGCAGAAUAUUGCAACUUUGUGUUGUUUUAUGAUGAGCCUAUAGUUGUGAUACCAAUAAAACAUGUCACUAGUUUCCAAA